GACGUCACGGGCCGGAGGUCCCGGGGCUGCUGGGUGCGGGCGGUGGGCUGCGCGUUGUCCGCUGGACUGGGUCCCGGUCACGCCCCGCCAAGCCCCGCCCCUCAGGCCGGGGCGCGACCGCGGAUCCGCAGUUCCCGGGCCAGCCUGGGGCGGCCGGCCAGGAACCACCCGUUAAGGGUCUUACUCUGUUGCCCAGGCUGGAGUGCAGUGGCACCAUCUCAGCUCACUGGAGCGUCUGCCUCCAGGUUCAAGUGAUUCUCCUGCCUCAGCAUCCCAAGUAGCUGGGACUACAGGUGUGCACUACCACUCCUGUCUAAUGUUUGUAUUUUUUGGUAGAGACAGGGUUUCCCUAUGUUGGCCAGUCUGGUCUUGAACUGCUGGCCUCAAGUGAUCUGCCCGCCUCGGCCUCCUAAAGUGCUGGGAUUACAGAAUUAACUCCUAGAAUUCUGACAGGCGGUAGUGCUUUGCAAGCUUUGUGUUAAGAGCUGCUACUGGGGAAUAUGUUGUUGCUGUACCUUCCACUAGGGUGGCAUUGAUCUCAUUAAGACAGAAAUUAUGUGUCUUCUCUUUAGGGAUGGUGAGGUUGGAAAAAGGCUCCUGUAACCCUCCUCCAGGAUGAACCACCUGCCAGAAGACAUGGAGAACGCUCUCACCGGGAGCCAGAGCUCCCAUGCUUCUCUGCGCAAUAUCCAUUCCAUCAACCCCACACAACUCAUGGCCAGGAUUGAGUCCUAUGAAGGAAGGGAAAAGAAAGGCAUAUCUGAUGUCAGGAGGACUUUCUGUUUGUUUGUCACCUUUGACCUCUUAUUCGUAACAUUACUGUGGAUAAUAGAGUUAAAUGUGAAUGGAGGCAUUGAGAACACAUUAGAGAAGGAGGUGAUGCAGUAUGACUACUAUUCUUCAUAUUUUGAUAUAUUUCUUCUGGCAGUUUUUCGAUUUAAAGUGUUAAUACUUGCAUAUGCUGUGUGCAGACUGCGCCAUUGGUGGGCAAUAGCGCUUUUCUCUCAAGGGGCUUUUGGCUAUGUGCUGCCCAUCAUUUCAUUCAUCCUUGCCUGGAUUGAGACGUGGUUCCUGGAUUUCAAAGUGUUACCUCAAGAAGCAGAAGAAGAAAACAGACUCCUGAUAGUUCAGGAUGCUUCAGAGAGGGCAGCACUUAUACCUGGUGGUCUUUCUGAUGGUCAGUUUUAUUCCCCUCCUGAAUCCGAAGCAGGAUCUGAAGAAGCUGAAGAAAAACAGGACAGUGAGAAACCACUUUUAGAACUAUGAGUACUACUUUUGUUAAAUGUGAAAAACCCUCACAGAAAGUCAUCGAGGCAAAAAGAGGCAGGCAGUGGAGUCUCCCUGUCGACAGUAAAGUUGAAAUGGUGACGUCCACUGCUGGCUUUAUUGAACAGCUAAUAAAGAUUUAUUUAUUGUAAUACCUCACAGACGUUGUACCAUAUCCAUGCACAUUUAGUUGCCUGCCUGUGGCUGGUAAGGUAAUGUCAUGAUUCAUCCUCUCUUCAGUGAGACUGAGCCUGAUGUGUUAACAAAUAGGUGAAGAAAGUCUUGUGCUGUAUUCCUAAUCAAAAGACUUAAUAUAUUGAAGUAACACUUUUUUAGUAAGCAAGAUACCUUUUUAUUUCAAUUCACAGAAUGGAAUUUUUUUGUUUCAUGUCUCAGAUUUAUUUUGUAUUUCUUUUUUAACACUCUACAUUUCCCUUGUUUUUUAACUCAUGCACAUGUGCUCUUUGUACAGUUUUAAAAAGUGUAAUAAAAUCUGACAUGUCAAUGUGGCUAGUUUUAUUUUUCUUGUUUUGCAUUAUGUGUAUGGCCUGAAGUGUUGGACUUGCAAAAGGGGAAGAAAGGAAUUGCGAAUACAUGUAAAAUGUCACCAGACAUUUGUAUUAUUUUUAUCAUGAAAUCAUGUUUUUCUCUGAUUGUUCUGAAAUGUUCUAAAUACUCUUAUUUUGAAUGCACAAAAUGACUUAAACCAUUCAUAUCAUGUUUCCUUUGCGUUCAGCCAAUUUCAAUUAAAAUGAACUAAAUUA